CCUGCCUAACUCCAGAGAUAGGGGCAGGGGUCCCCUCUGCAGGCUGCCCCCUUUGCCCUUCCAUGCCACCCUGGGCCUGUUCCUACCACACUUCCCAUGUUCCCAUGAUCCCACUCCUUGGUCCAAGGUCAAGUUUCUCCAGGAAAUGGAGUGCGCGGGCCCGUGGUGGGGGGAAGAUGUCCCCCUACACCAACUGCUAUGCCCAGCGCUACUACCCCAUGCCAGAAGAGCCCUUCUGCACAGAACUCAACGCUGAGGAGCAGGCCCUGAAGGAGAAGGAGAAGGGAAGCUGGACCCAGCUGACCCACGCCGAAAAGGUGGCCUUGUACCGGCUCCAGUUCAAUGAGACCUUUGCGGAGAUGAACCGUCGCUCCAAUGAGUGGAAGACAGUGAUGGGUUGUGUCUUCUUCUUCAUUGGAUUCGCAGCUCUGGUGAUUUGGUGGCAGCGGGUCUACGUAUUUCCUCCAAAGCCGAUCACCUUGACGGACGAGCGGAAAGCCCAGCAGCUGCAGCGCAUGCUGGACAUGAAGGUGAAUCCUGUGCAGGGCCUGGCCUCCCGCUGGGACUAUGAGAAGAAGCAGUGGAAGAAGUGACUUGCAUCCCCAGCUGUCUCCCUGAGGCUCCGCCCUGGCUGGGAGCCUCUGGCGGCCCCUCCCCUCCCCUGCCCUUAACCCCAGUAAAGCUCCAAAAAAAAA